CCCAACCAGUAUUCAUCCAAGGAGCACACUUGGAUGAAUAAAGGCAAACGGAAGUAAGUAGUAUUAAAACAAGGUACAGGCCCAGUGUGAUGGCUCAAAUCUCUAAUCCCAACACUGGGAGGCUGAGGUGGGAGAAUCACUUGAGCCUAGGAGUUCAAGAUCAGCCUGAGUUACAUAGCAAGUCUCCUUCUCUACAAAAAAUGAAAUUAGCCAAGUAUAAUGGCACAUGCCUAUAGUCCCAGCUACUGGGGAGGGAGGCUGAGGCAAGAGAAUCACUUGAGCCCAAGAGUUUGAGGCUGCAAUGAGCUAUGAUUGUGACACUGCACUUUAGCCUAGGCAACAGAGUGAGCCUCUGUUUCCAAAAAAAAAAAGGUACAAGAGGUUGUGCCUAAUUCUGCUUUGUGUAGUAAGAUUUGUAAACCAGGUUGUUGAUAGAUGAAGAGAAAUUUACCAUAUGCAGUAAGAAAGCAAGGUAGGAACCUGUAGCCUAGACCAAGGCAUAUGCAAAUACUGCAUGUUCAAGAAAUAGUGACAUUGAAUUGAAUGAACCAGAGUUUCGGGUGCCUGAAGCAGAGUAAUAGGGCAGGAAGCUGCAUAAAAAGAUGGGCCUGGUUGUGAAGAGCCUCCUUAUGAGAGAAGCAGCUAGGAAUCAACAGUUUCAGAAACUGGAGAGCAAGUAUCAUGAAGAUAUAAAUGGGUUGAUGGAUUUGUACAUAAGGUGAUACUUGUAUACUUAAUGAGAAAUUUUUCUAUAGCAUGAUAGAUGGUGGAAAUUAUAUAGGAAUUGGAUAGAUGUGAAUUUUAUGAGUAUUUGACUUUAGUGGAAGUGUAUUUGGUCUCAAAAGAGGAAGGAGAUAAAGGUUUUUGUUUUGAUUUUGUUUGUUAAAGAUGGGAGAUUUCAGCAUGUAUCUAAGCAAAUGAAAGAAGUGGAAAAGAAAUGAGAUGGAUGAGAAAAGGAGAAGAGAGUCACCUGUUUAGGGAAGUAUGGAGAUGCUAAACCUGGCCAUGAUCACGGGGAGCAUUUUGCUAAUGCUGAAACAAAGUACGUGUGUGCUUAUUAACAUAUAGCAUUUCUAAGUUAGUCCUGGGAAUAAAAUGGGUAAGCUCUAGCCAAAAUUCUCUUUCCCAAGUAAUACAUUAUCUCCACAGAGCAUUCAUUACAUUAUUUGUUUCAUUGACUUUCUUCCCUAAUGGGUGUCAAACCUGUGUCUGAUUCUUAGGCCUCAGGUACUAGUACAAUGCUAGGUGAAUUAGGAAAAUGGCCUCUGAUCCAUAGCUGCUUUUCACGCAAAAACCUACAGAAGUCUGCUGAAAAGGUAUUUGGAUAAUUAAACAAGACCGAAAAGUAAUGACUAAUGACAGAGAAUCUUGCAAACUGAAGGUCUCUGCCCAGGCAGGGAAACGAACUAAUCAAUAUUCAACAGUUACGUGUGCUGUUUUUCAGUGCUCUCGAUGCCUUGGGAAAGAAGGGGACAUGGUGUAAUCACAGUAUUAAGGGGAAAGUGGUUGAAAUGUUUCCUGAGCGCUCUCAUUCAACUUUUGCUCCGUUCACAGCCUGAUGCUACAGGCUCGGCCCCGAGGUUAUACCCACCAAGAGGAAGUAUGUCCGGAAUUGGUGGGUUCUUGCAGUCACUGACUUCAAGAAUGAAGCCGCGGACCCUCGCGGUGCAGCAUUGUACUGCAAGUCAAUCGAUACAAUAAUUUAAGUCACUUCAGCUAUAAUGGAAAAGUAUGAAAAAUUAGCUAAGACUGGAGAAGGGUCUUAUGGGGUUGUAUUCAAAUGCAGAAACAAAACCUCUGGACAAGUAGUAGCUGUUAAAAAAUUUGUGGAAUCUGAAGAUGAUCCUGUUGUUAAGAAAAUAGCACUAAGAGAAAUACGUAUGUUGAAGCAAUUAAAACAUCCAAAUCUUGUGAACCUCAUCGAGGUGUUCAGGAGAAAAAGGAAAAUGCAUUUAGUUUUUGAAUACUGUGAUCAUACACUUUUAAAUGAGCUGGAAAGAAACCCAAAUGGAGUUGCUGAUGGAGUGAUCAAAAGCGUAUUAUGGCAAACACUUCAAGCUCUUAAUUUCUGUCAUAUACAUAACUGUAUUCACAGAGAUAUAAAACCUGAAAAUAUUCUAAUAACUAAGCAAGGAAUAAUCAAGAUUUGUGACUUCGGGUUUGCACAAAUUCUGAUUCCAGGAGAUGCCUACACCGAUUAUGUAGCUACGAGAUGGUACCGAGCUCCUGAACUUCUUGUGGGAGAUACUCAGUAUGGUUCUUCAGUCGAUAUAUGGGCUAUUGGUUGUGUUUUUGCAGAGCUCCUGACAGGCCAGCCACUGUGGCCUGGAAAAUCAGAUGUGGACCAACUUUAUCUGAUAAUCAGAACACUAGGAAAAUUAAUCCCAAGACAUCAAUCAAUCUUUAAAAGUAACGGGUUUUUCCAUGGCAUCAGUAUACCUGAGCCAGAAGACAUGGAAACUCUUGAGGAAAAGUUCUCAGAUGUUCAUCCUGUGGCUCUGAACUUCAUGAAGGGGUGUCUGAAGAUGAAUCCAGAUGACAGAUUAACCUGUUCCCAACUCCUGGAGAGCUCCUACUUUGAUUCUUUUCAAGAGGCCCAAAUUAAAAGAAAAGCACGUAAUGAAGGAAGAAACAGAAGACGCCAACAGCAGGCACCUAAGUCUGCCUUUCCUAGGCUUUUUCUCAAAACCAAGAUCUGCCAGGUACAAAGGAAUGAAACCCAGACAUCUGGGAACCAAAUUCUACCCAAUGGGCCAAUAUUGCAGAACAGUAUGGUGACUGUUAUGACAAACAUUAAUUCUGCAGUUUAUCAGGUGACUGUCCUUCACUUGCUUUCAGAAAACUUUGAAGUUAAAUCGUAAACUCCAUGGAAAUAGGUUUGUUUUGGUUCAGGGCUUUUUCUCACCUUGUAAACCCGGCACCUAAAACAGUAUCUGACACAGAGAAGGUCCCUAAUAUUAUUAAAAUAAAUAAGUAGACGAACAUUGCCUAAUAAUAAACUGAGUUGGUAAUUUCCAAUUC